AGUGUUUUGACAGGGCAAACAGCAGAGAAAGAACUGGCCGAGCGAGGGGGACGGGGAGCCGGGGCGCCAGAGCUAGAGACAGCGGGCGGGCAAGGAGCUGGCAGAGGCGCUGGGCAAGAGGGCCGGCCGGGGCUACGGGCGGGGGAAGCCCGGGGGUCGCGGGGCUCGGGUGCCAGUCAGGCAGGGCGGAGGGGCUGAGCGCAGGGAGCGGAGCGAGGCGGUGGCUGAGGCGCGGGUGGAUGGCCACAGGGGCGCCGGGGAGCCGCUUCGGGCUGGUCGUCUCGGGUCCCCACGGUCACCUGAGGCAGCCGCGGGGGCCGCUGCGCUCCAUACUCCGCUCCCGCUGGCCCUGCGCCUCUCGGAGCCUGGGGUCUGAGGUGGGAGUGUGAUGUGAGCUGCUGGGCGAGCGGUGGAGAGAAGUGCCAAGAGGAGGCGGGAUUGGGACGGGAGAGGAGAGCGAGUUAGUCAGCAGAGGUCGGCCGAGGGAGCGGAGGAGCCGGCCAGCUCGAGAGCGCCAUGAAAACAACUCUCCAGCGGGGAGAGGGGCAGACGCGGCGCUCGCAUUUUGAAAGCGAAGCAGAAGCCGUAGAAUCAGCGGCGAGCCUGUUGAAAGAACCCACAGGUGCAUUUCACAGCACUCUGGGCGAAAAUUGGAUGUGAAAAUGAAGCCAGACCGAGAUACUCUGGAUGAAUAUUUUGAAUAUGAUGCAGAGGAGUUCUUGGUCUCUUUGGCCUUGCUGAUAACAGAAGGACGAACACCUGAAUGUUCUGUAAAAGGUCGAACAGAAAGCUUUCAUUGCCCUCCAGCACAGUCUUGUUACCCAGUAACUACCAAACAUGAAUGUAGUGACAAGCUGGCCCAGUGCCGCCAAGCCAGACGAACUAGGUCUGAGGUCACAUUGUUGUGGAAGAAUAACCUUCCAAUCAUGGUGGAAAUGAUGCUACUACCAGACUGCUGCUACAGCGAUGAUGGGCCCACCACAGAGGGAAUUGAUCUAAAUGAUCCUGCGAUUAAGCAAGAUGCAUUAUUAUUAGAAAGAUGGAUCUUGGAGCCAGUUCCUCGACAGAAUGGUGACCGAUUUAUUGAAGAGAAGACGCUUCUGUUGGCUGUCCGCUCAUUUGUGUUUUUUUCUCAGUUAAGUGCAUGGCUGAGUGUUUCUCAUGGUGCUAUUCCACGAAAUAUUCUCUACAGAAUCAGUGCUGCUGAUGUAGACCUACAGUGGAAUUUUUCACAGACUCCAAUUGAGCAUGUGUUUCCUGUUCCCAAUGUUUCUCACAAUGUUGCCUUGAAAGUCAGUGUUCAGUCCUUGCCCAGACAAUCUAAUUAUCCAGUUUUGACGUGCAGUAUUCACACUAAUAUUGGCCUUUAUGAGAAAAGAAUUCAACAACAUAAACUUAAAACUCAUCAGCACCAUAACCCAAAUGAAGCAGAACAAUGUGGUACAAACAGUUCACAGCGUCUGUGUAGCAAACAAACUUGGACCAUGGCACCUGAAAGUGUGUUACAUGCAAAAAGUGGCCCAAGUCCAGAAUAUACUGCAGCUGUCAAAAAUAUCAAACUAUAUCCAGGCACUGGCAGUAAAUCUGACCAUGGGACAUCUCAAGCCAAUAUUCUAGGCUUUAGUGGUAUAGGUGAUAUAAAAUCACAAGAAACAUCAGUGAGAACUUUAAAAUCAUUUUCAAUGGUUGAUUCCAGUAUCUCUAACCGCCAGAGUUUCUGGCAGUCAGCUGGUGAGACUAACCCUUUAAUAGGCUCUUUAAUUCAGGAGCGGCAAGAAAUCAUUGCAAGAAUUGCCCAACAUUUGAUUCAUUGUGAUCCAAGCACUUCACAUGUUUCUGGACGUCCAUUUAAUACUCAAGAGUCUAGUUCACUCCAUUCAAAACUUUUCCGGGUUUCACAAGAAAAUGAGAACGUGGGAAAAGGUAAAGAAGCUUUCUCCAUGACUUUUGGUAGUCCAGAGUUUAGUUCCCCAGAAGACACCAAUGAGGGGAAAAUUCGACUAAAACCAGAAACUCCUCGAAGUGAAACUUGUAUUUCUAAUGACUUUUAUUCUCAUAUGCCUGUUGGAGAGACUAAUCCUUUGAUAGGCUCUUUACUCCAGGAGCGGCAAGAUGUUAUUGCAAGGAUUGCUCAACACUUGGAGCACAUUGAUCCAACAGCAUCACAUAUCCCCCGGCAGUCAUUCAACAUGCAUGACUCCAGUUCGGUUGCAUCUAAAGUGUUUAGGAGUUCAUAUGAAGACAAAAAUUUGUUGAAGAAAAAUAAGGAUGAGUCCUCAGUUUCCAUUUCUCACACAAAAUGUUCCUUGUUAGGAGACAUCAGUGAUGGGAAAAACUUAGUACCUAAUAAAUGUUUUACUUCUUUUAAAAAUAAUAGUAAAGAAAAGUGUUCUUUGAAACAUCAAACAAGAAAUCAGUGUCAGAACAAUCCUAGUGAAAUCAUCCAAAGUACGUAUCAGGAGACACAGAACAAAAGUUCUAGUUUAUCAACUUCCUCAAUUUUGUCUCAGCACAAAGAAAAUAACUUAGAUUUGACAAGCAGAUUCAAGGAGCAAGAAAUGAGCAAUGGAAUUGAUAAACAGUAUUCAAAUUGCACCACUAUUGACAAACAGAUUUGUACAAAUAAGUAUAAGGAAAAAAUAAUAAAUGAGAACUAUAAUCCAAAAUUCUUUGGCAAUCUUCAGUCUGAUGAUUCCAAAAAAAAUGACUCAAAAAUAAAAGUUACUGUGUUGGAAAUGUCUGAAUAUUUGAACAAAUAUGAAAGCAUGUCCUCAAAUAAAGACUCAAAAAGGCCUAAGACAUGUGAGCAAAAUACUCAACUUAAUAGCAUAGAGAAUUAUCUCAAUAAAGAUAAUGAAGGUUUCAAAUGUAAAAAGUCAGACCAAUUAAAAAAUGAACAAGAUAAGCAAGAAGAUCCAACUAAUGAAAAAUCCCAAAACUAUUCUCAGAGAAGAAGUAUAAAAGACUGUUUGUCUACAUGUGAGCAACCAAAAAAUACAGAGGUAUUGAGGACUACACUGAAACAUUCAAAUGUGUGGCGAAAACAUAAUUUUCAUUCCUUGGAUGGAACUUCAACCAGAGCCUUUCAUCCUCAAACUGGAUUGCCUCUUCUUUCAAGCCCUGUUCCUCAAAGAAAAACACAAUCAGGUUGCUUUGAUCUGGAUUCUUCAUUACUACAUCUGAAAAGCUUCUCAUCUAGAAGUCCUCGACCAUGUUUAAACAUUGAAGAUGAUCCAGAUAUUCAUGAAAAACCAUUUUUGAGUUCUAGUGCUCCACCUAUAACAAGUCUUAGUCUCCUAGGAAAUUUUGAGGAAUCUGUCUUGAACUAUCGUUUCGAUCCUCUCGGCAUUGUUGAUGGUUUUACUGCCGAGGUAGGGGCAAGUGGUGCUUUCUGCCCCACACAUUUGACUCUUCCAGUUGAAGUGUCAUUCUACAGUGUUUCAGAUGACAAUGCUCCCUCUCCUUAUAUGGGUGUGAUUACUUUAGAGUCCCUUGGUAAAAGGGGUUAUCGAGUACCUCCUUCAGGAACAAUACAAGUGACCUUAUUUAAUCCUAAUAAGACUGUGGUGAAGAUGUUUGUUGUGAUAUAUGAUUUACGAGAUAUGCCAGCCAAUCAUCAGACAUUCCUACGACAAAGAACUUUUUCUGUACCUGUUAAACAAGAAGUGAAGAGAAGUGUUAAUAAAGAGAACAUCCGACACACAGAAGAACGGUUAUUACGCUACCUCAUACAUCUGAGGUUCCAGAGUUCUAAAUCUGGAAAGAUCUACCUCCAUAGAGACGUACGGCUCCUGUUCUCUAGAAAGUCAAUGGAGGUUGAUAGCGGUGCUGCAUAUGAACUCAAAUCUUACACUGAAUCACCAACAAACCCUCAGUUUUCACCAAGAUGUUGAUAAGGAGUGAUGAUUUAAAGUAUUUACUCAGUACCCAAGUUUGCAAGUAAAAAUUAGCAUAGAAUGGAGUGUACCAAAUUAACAAUCAGGAGAGUGGAUUCUCUCCUGUUAUCCUGGACCAGUUUUUAUGAAAGGAUUCCUGAAAUGAAAUCCAUAUAUUCCAUGUAGACUGGAAAAACUCAUGUCCUAAUCCUUUUUGUACUGUUGAAACCACUUCAUUGGACAUGUUGCAAUAGCAAAACCCCCAGUUAGAUUAGUGUUUACACAUUUUCUCAGUUAUUUAAUAUUUAAUGUUUUCCUUAAUACUCAAGUGAUGUUUGUCUCUAGUGUUCUAAUGUAGCACAAAUCCUAUGUAAAAUCAUACUAUGUAUUUUUGACAUUAAUGUUGAAAUCAAAUAUAUGCACAAGUCUUUAAUUUUGUGUAAUGUGUUAAGUGCUGUUCAUUUAAGUUAUUGAAAAUGAGAAUAAAAUGUUGAGCUUCUUUAAAAGUAACACACUAUGCAAGCAUGUGUACUUUUUAUAUCUCUCAUGUUUAGUUUUUAUAACACCAUAUCCAGGUUGCUAUCUCACAUAGUAGUCCUUUAACAUAUUGUAUUAGCAGUGCAAUGUGGACUAAGCUGCUUCACUUUCCCUUUGCAAGUUCAGAUCAUCAUGCCCAUUCAUAGCCAGGAUUCCUUAUCCCCAAAACAGUUCUAUUUUUCCUUAAUCACUACUAUAGAGUCUUUACAUUAAAUUACUGUCGUAUGCUAGAUAAUUUUCUCAAAUUGUUAAAAGAAUAUGUACUUUGGAAACAAAUUAGUAUUUAUAUUGUAAAUAUAUUCAAAAAAAACUAA